AUUCACAAUGGCUAAAACAGGCCGGGUGUGGUGGCUCACGCCUGUAAUCCCAGCGCUUUGGGAGGCUGAGGCUGACAGAUCAUCUGAGGUCAGGAGUUCAAGACCAGCCUGGCCAACAUGCUGAAAACCUGUCUCUACUAAAAAUGCAAAAUUUAGCCAGGCGUGGUGGUGGGUGCCUGUAAUCUCAGCUACUCCGGAGGCUGAGACAGGAGAAUGGCCUGGACCCAGGAGGCGGAAGUUGCAGUAAGCCGAGAUCGUGUCACUUCACUCCAGCCUGGACAACAGAGUGAGACUCUGUCUCGAAAAAAAAAAAGGACAAAAUGCUGUAGGAUUCCACUGAUAUGACGUACCUGGAGUCAGCAGAGCCACAGAGACAGAUGGUAGAAUGCCCGCAGGGCCCCGGACCCCGGCUUCCAGGAGCGCUUCUUCCAGCAGCGUCUGGACCACUUCAACUUCGAGCGCUUCGGCAACAAGACCUUCCCUCAGCGCUUCCUGGUGUCGGACAGGUUCUGGGUCCGGGGCGAGGGGCCCAUCUUCUUCUACACUGGGAACGAGGGCGACGUGUGGGCCUUCGCCAACAACUCGGCCUUCGUCGCGGAGCUGGCGGCCGAGCGGGGGGCUCUACUGGUCUUCGCGGAGCACCGCUACUACGGGAAGUCGCUGCCGUUCGGUGCGCAGUCCACGCAGCGCGGGCACACGGAGCUGCUGACGGUGGAGCAGGCCCUGGCCGACUUCGCAGAGCUGCUCCGCGCGCUACGACGCGACCUCGGGGCCCAGGAUGCCCCCGCCAUCGCCUUCGGUGGAAGGGAGCCUACGACACGGUCCGCUGGGAGUUCGGCACCUGCCAGCCGCUGUCAGACGAGAAGGACCUGACCCAGCUCUUCAUGUUCGCCCGGAAUGCCUUCACCGUGCUGGCCAUGAUGGACUACCCCUACCCCACUGACUUCCUGGGUCCCCUCCCUGCCAACCCCGUCAAGGUGGGCUGUGAUCGGCUGCUGAGUGAGGCCCAGAGGAUCACGGGGCUGCGAGCACUGGCAGGGCUGGUCUACAACGCCUCGGGCUCCGAGCACUGCUACGACAUCUACCGGCUCUACCACAGCUGUGCUGACCCCACUGGCUGCGGCACCGGCCCCGACGCCAGGGCCUGGGACUACCAGGCCUGCACCGAGAUCAACCUGACCUUCGCCAGCAACAAUGUGACCGAUAUGUUCCCGGACCUGCCCUUCACUGACGAGCUCCGCCAGCGGUACUGCCUGGACACCUGGGGCGUGUGGCCCCGGCCCGACUGGCUGCUGACCAGCUUCUGGGGGGGUGAUCUCAGAGCCGCCAGCAACAUCAUCUUCUCCAACGGGAACCUGGACCCCUGGGCAGGGGGCGGGAUUCGGAGGAACCUGAGUGCCUCAGUCAUCGCCGUCACCAUCCAGGGGGGAGCGCACCACCUCGACCUCAGAGCCUCCCACCCAGAAGAUCCUGCUUCCGUGGUUGAGGCGCGGAAGCUGGAGGCCACCAUCAUCGGCGAGUGGGUAAAGGCAGCCAGGCGUGAGCAGCAGCCAGCUCUGCGUGGGGGGCCCAGACUCAGCCUCUGAGCACAGGACUGGAGGGGUCUCAAGGCUCCUCAUGGAGUGGGGGCUUCACUCAAGCAGCUGGCGGCAGAGGGAAGGGGCUGAAUAAACGCCUGGAGGCCUGGC